AAUCUUCUUUAUAGGACCUUUUACUCCGAUAGGGUUUCCAGAGGGCUCCACUGUGACUGCUUCAGAGCUGGGGGACAUCGCCGUCUUAAUUCACAUGGUAUCCUCGCAACUGAGGAAGAGGAGCCAAAAAGCACCAAAAGCAGAAACAAAACAACUCUGAAAAAGCAUUCCUCAAAAGCCCUGUGCAUUCAAAAAAGGCUUGGUUGGGUUAUUUCCAGUUGUACUGUCGAGAAAAGAGCUAUUUCUGUCUUUUAACUCUCAAAUACAAAGAUACUGCUCAGUGGGAAUCAAACAUUCCUAAUUUUCAUUUAUUUAUCUUUUCAUUUUAAUUUUGGAUUGGGGGGGGUAUCUGCGCAGCUCUGUUAGACGGAGUAUAUUGCAUGGUGCUGAGGUCUGGGCUUCUGAUGGUCCCGUCGUUCAAGUAGCAAACGCGCUGCGCGAAAGCUAAGGCGGGUCUUUGGAAAUUGCCUGCCACCCUUCCCACCAAAGUACUAUCUGGCAAUGACCACAGCUAUGGCUGAUGAGAGGAGGGACCAACUGGAACAAUAUUUGCAAAAUGUAACCAUGGACCCAAACGUGUUGAGAAGUGAUGUCUUCGUUGAGUUUUUAAAACUGGCGCAGCUGAAUACAUUUGACAUCGCCACCAAGAAAGCUUAUCUGGACAUAUUUCUGCCCAAUGAACAGAGUAUUAGAAUCGAAAUUAUAACAUCAGACACUGCUGAAAGAGUCCUAGAGGUGGUGUCACACAAAAUUGGACUGUGUCGAGAGCUCUUGGGCUACUUCGGCCUCUUUCUCAUUCGGUUUGGCAAGGAGGGCAAGCUCUCUGUUGUGAAAAAAUUGGCUGACUUUGAACUCCCUUAUGUUAGUCUUGGAAGUUCUGAGGUGGAAAACUGUAAGGUUGGACUCCGAAAGUGGUAUAUGGCUCCAUCCCUCGACUCCGUGCUGAUGGACUGCAGGGUGGCGGUAGAUUUGCUCUACAUGCAGGCAAUACAGGACAUUGAAAAAGGAUGGGCCAAACCCACACAGGCACAGAGGCAGAAAUUAGAAGCUUUCCAGAAAGAAGACAGUCAAACAAAGUUUUUGGAGCUGGCCCGGGAGGUACGGCACUAUGGAUACCUGCAGCUGGAUCCUUGUACCUGUGACUACCCAGAAUCAGGCUCUGGAGCUGUUCUUUCUGUUGGCAAUAAUGAGAUCAGCUGCUGCAUCACCCUGCCUGACAGCCAGACCCAGGACAUCGUUUUCCAGAUGAGCAGGGUGAAGUGCUGGCAGGUCACUUUCCUUGGAACUCUGCUGGAUACGGAUGGGCCCCAGAGAACUCUCAACCAGAACUUAGAGCUCAGAUUUCAAUACAGUGAGGAUAGUUGCUGGCAGUGGUUUGUUAUUUACACCAAACAGGCUUUUUUGCUGAGUAGCUGCUUGAAAAAGAUGAUCUCAGAAAAGAUGGUAAAGCUAGCUGCUGAGAAUACAGAAAUGCAGAUUGAAGUUCCGGAACAAAGCAAAAGUAAAAAAUACCACAUUCAACAAAGCCAGCAGAAAGACUAUUCUAGUUUUCUAUCAAGAAAAAGCAAGAUUAAGAUAGCUAAAGAUGACUGCGUUUUUGGGAACAUAAAGGAAGAAGAUCUCUGAAGAAAGCUCUCAUAUUUUAAAAUAUCCUUGGAGGCUAUCUCAAGACAGUGAAAGAACUUGGGGAUUCAGGUGGGCUACCUACCAUCAGUGGAGGAAAUUUGACCUCUUCCCAUUUUUUUGGCAUUAACAUGGACUGUAUUCAUCAAGGUAUUAUACCACAGCACUCUAUGGAAAUCUCAAGAUUAGAAAAAAAAAAAGAACCAAGUUAUAGAGUUAGUUUUUAUUUUAUUUUUGCACUUCGUCAUGACAGUAUAGAGUUUGUUUUUAAUGUCUCAUAAAUGACAAGUGGCAAAUUCAAAUCAACUCAUAUAAAACUCAUUCUAUUUUUUCUCUAAAAUAGAUCUUUAUAUGGCUUCAUGAAGUCUUUUAUGUGUUUUGAAUUUACAUAAAUGAAAGUCUCAUAAAAUAUCAUAAAGAUAUUUUGGAUCGAUUUCUAAAGAUGUGACUCUUCAACGGAGGAGAAUAGGGCUCUGAGAAAUGGAAUCACUGAAAAAGAAACCUGGGUUCUCUGAUCUAUCCACACAGAACUAGAGCAAGGAGGUGAUGAAAUACUGAUCUCUUUCCUCACAUAAGUCUGAGCCUACCAAUAUGGAUGUACUCAAAGUGAAACGCUGCCCUGUUCUCUGCUUGACCAUUGUUAUAAUUUUAUUCUGUCCUUAGAGUACUGAAGGCAGUUCAAUAAUCAACAUGCUAUUUGGAAUGUUUUAAUUUGGAAAGCAAUAAGGCUCUGCACCUGAUAUCAGAUACCUUAUAAUUCUCUUAGCUUUAAAAAUAUGUAUACUUUCUCACAAGGUUUUUCCUUAUCUAGCUUCAUUUCUCUCAUGGUAAUUAAUGUAAUUAUGUAUAGAAUUAAGACCACAAUAAGGGAGAUGAUCAGAGGAAUCUGUAUAGUGUAAUUAGAAAAAGUACAAUAUUCUAAUGUUCUAACUGGGUUGUAUACCUAAUUAUAUAAUAAAUACAAAAUAAUUCCAGUGAAUAUAAAAUUUGUUGA